GAGUUUCGACAUGUCUUCCCAAGCUUUCCCAGCUGAAGAGGAUCAUCAUAAUGAAGAAAGACAAACAAAGAAAAAAAGAAAAACAAAACACCGACAUAAAUUUUCUGAAGAAUUAUUGCAGGAACUUAAGGAAAUAUUUGGAGAGAACGGUUAUCCUGAUUUCACCACUAGGAAAACACUGGCCAACAAAUUUGAUUGUCCGGUUAACGUGAUAAACAACUGGUUCCAGAACAAUAGAGCCAGACUUCCACCGGAAGAAAGACAAAGAAUAUUUCUUACUUGGAAAAAACACGAUUUCCCAGUCCAAGCCUGUCCAUUUUUAAGCCUCCAGGAAACCCAGGCUGCAGCUUCCAACUAUGCCACAGAGCAGAGUUUUUCCUGUGCCAAGAGGGCUCUGAUGAGAAGACCUGGUUGCUCCCUUCUGGAGAAACAGAGGAUUGCCUGUCAACAGAUGGGCUACAAUUGCUUCUCUUUGGAGAACCAAGAGACUCCCAGUCAACAGGUGGGCUCCAUGUGCUCUUCUCUGGAGAAACAAGGGAUUCCCAGUCAACAGGUGGGUUCCCAGUGCUCCUAUCUGGUCGCAGGUACUGAAAAGCAUCCAGGCUAUGCUUUGGAGUAUGGAGGUGACACAGGAAGUGAGCAUUCUACUGCCUAUCGUUUUCUCAGCUACAACUCUGCAGAAUGCCUUCAUCCUCCCCCAUCUUCUGUGCCAUAUUUUCAUGGAGAAAGGACUGAAACCAGGGAAAGCCAGCAUGCAAGUCCCUUCCUUUUGGAUUACGCUCAAGGUGCUUACGGGGUGAAGAAAGACCAUUGUCUUUGCUCAUUCUGUCUCUCACUGCUGCAAGAACAGCAGCAGAAUGAUUGGCAGUAUCACCCACAGCAGCACCAACAGCCUCAGAAUUACUCAGAGGGGAUGAUGUUGCAGGAACAGCUGCCAAUGGACUCGGGUCCUUGGGAUCUAGAGAAGCAGUGGCCCUCGGCUCAGUCACAGCUGCAGAGUCAACUGCCUCAGAAUAAUGGAAAGCCGUUGUGCUCUCAACUGCAGCACGUGCCUCCCCAAAUAGCUGCCAACUCACCCCUGCUGCCUCUGGGGCAAGAUAUGCAGGUAGGGGCUUCAAGCAACUCAGGACUCAAAUGCAGCAGUUUUAGGUUGAGGGGUCUACACGGGCCUGCCACAGGAACCCAAGGAUGCAGCUUUGCAAAGUAUUGCUAAGUAUCACAGAACCAUAGCCACAGGUCA